CUUCCUCUCCUCGUACGGAGUUCAAGAUGGCGGCCUCCUGGUCGCUCUUGGUUACCCUGCGCCCCUUAGCACAGAGCCCGCUGAGAGGGAGAUGUGUUGGGUGCGGGGCCUGGGCCGCCGCUCUCGCUCCUCUGGCCACCGCCCCUGGGAAGCCCUUUUGGAAAGCCUAUACGGUUCAGACAUCCGAGAGCAUGACCCCAACUGCCACUUCAGAGACUUAUUUGAAAGCUUUGGCCGUUUGCCAUGGACCUCUGGACCACUAUGAUUUUCUGAUCAAAGCUCAUGAGCUAAAGGAUGAUGAACAUCAAAGAAGAGUCAUACAGUGUUUGCAGAAAUUACACGAGGACCUUAAAGGAUACAAUAUAGAGGCAGAAGGCCUUUUUUCAAAGCUUUUUUCAAGGAGCAAACCUCCAAGGGGCCUGUAUGUUUAUGGAGAUGUUGGUACAGGAAAAACAAUGGUGAUGGACAUGUUUUAUGCUUAUGUGGAAAUGAAGAGGAAAAAACGGGUUCAUUUUCAUGGUUUCAUGCUAGAUGUGCACAAAAGAAUACAUCGCCUUAAACAGAGUUUGCCAAAAAGGAAACCAGGAUUCAUGGCUAAAUCAUAUGACCCAAUAGCUCCCAUAGCCGAAGAAAUCAGCGAAGAAGCAUGUCUCCUAUGUUUUGAUGAAUUUCAGGUCACUGACAUUGCUGAUGCCAUGAUUCUGAAACAGCUUUUUGAAAAUCUGUUCAAAAACGGGGUCGUCGUUGUGGCAACAUCCAACAGGCCACCGGAAGGUCCAGCUUUGGCAUGAGGCCCUCCAUCCAGAACAUCAUGGUCUGACUCAGCAUAUGCCAUGCUCUGCUCUUCUCAGUGGUUGCCUUGUGCCCAGAACUCAGCCUAGAUUUUUAUUUUUAUUUAUUUUUGUUUUUUACUUUUUUAUUUUUCAACUUCUGUCUUAGAUUCAGGGGGUACACGUGCAGGUUUGUUACCUAUAUAUAUUGCAUGAUGCUGAAGUUUGGGGUACAAAUGAUCCCAUCACCUAGGUACUGAGCAUAGUAUCUAACAGUUAGUUUUUCCACCCUUACCCGCUUCUACCCUUCCCCUCUAGUAGUCCCCCGUGUCUAUCAUUCCCAUCUUUAUGUCCAUGAGUACCCGAUGUCUAGCUCCCACUCAUAAGUGAGAACAUGUGGUAUAUGGUUUUUUUGUUCCUGCAUUAAUUCAUUUAGGCUAAUGGCCUCGAGCUGCAUCCAUGUUGCUGCAAAAGACAUGAUUUCAUUCUUUUUAUGGCUGUGUAGUACUCCUUGGUGUAUAUGUACCACAUUUUCCUCAUCCAGUCGUCAUUAAUGGGUACCUGGGUUGAUGCUAUGACUUUGCUAUUGUGAAUAGUGCUGUGAUGAAUGUGCAAAUGCAUGUCUUUUGGUAGAAUGAUUUGUUUUCUGUUGGAUAGACACCCAGUAAUGGGAUUGCUGGGUCAAAUGGUAGUUCUGAGAUUUUUUUUUUUUUUUUUUGAGAUGGAGUCUAGCUUUGUUACUCAGGCUGGAAUGCAGUGACAUGAUCUCGGCUCUGCCUCCCAGGUUCAAGUGAUUCUCCUGCGUCAGCCUCUCGAGUAGCUGGGACUACAGGCAUGCGCCACCAUGCCCGGCUAAUUUUUGUAGUUUUAGUAGAAGAUGGGGUUUCACCAUAUUGGCCAGACUGGUCUCGAACUCCUGACAUCAAGUGAUCCACUUGCCUCGGCCUCCCAAAGUGGUGGGAUUACAGGCGUGAGCCACUGCGCCUGGCCGGUAGUUCUGUUUUAAGUUUUUUGAGAUGUCUCCAAACUGCUUUCCACAGUGGCUGAACUAAUUUACAUUCCCACCAAUGGUGUAUAAGCAUUCCCUUUUCUCCACAGCCUCACCAGCAUCUGUUAUUUUUUACUUUUUAAUACAAGCCAUUCUGACUGGUGUGAGAUGGUAUCUCAUUGUGGUUUUCAUUUGUGUUUCUCUCGUGAUUGGUGAUGUGGAUUUUUUUUUAUAUGUUUGUUGGCCACUGUGUGUCUUCUUUUGAGAAGUGUCUGUUCAUUUCUUUUGCCCAUGUUUUAAUGGAGUUAUUUGUUUUUUGCUUGUUCAGUUGUUUAAUUUGCUUAUAGAUUCUGGAUAUUAGACCUUUGUCAGAUGCAUAGCUUGCAAAUAUUUUAUCCCUUUCUGUAGGUUGUCUCUUUACUCUGUGGAUAGUUGCUUUUACUGUGCAGAAGUUCUUUAGUUUAAUUAGGCCUUACUUACAAAUUUUUGUUUUUGUUGCAAUUGUUUUUGAGGACUUAGUAAUAAAUUGUUUCCCAAGACUGAUAUUCAGAAUGGUGUUCCCUAGAUUUUCAUCUAGGAUUCUUAUAGUUUGAAGUCUUACGUUUAAAUCUUUGAUUCAUCUUGAGUUAAUUUUUGCAUAUGGUGAAAGGUCCAGUUUCAUUCUUCGGCAUAUGGCUAGCCAGCUAUCCCAGCAUCAUUUAUUGAAUAGGGAGUCCUUUCCCCAUUGCUUAUUUUUGUCAACUUUGUUGAAUAUCAAAUGGCUUUAGGUGUAUAGCUUUAUUUCUGUGUUCCUUAUUUCAUUCCAUUGGUCUAUAUGUCUGUUUUGGUACCAGUACCAUGCUAUUUUGGUUACCAUAGCCUUAUGGUAUAGUUUGAAGUUGGUUAAUGUGAUGCCUUUGGCUUUGUUCCUUUUGUUUAGGGUUGCUUUGGUUAUUUUGGCUCCUUUUUGGUUCCAUAUGAAUUUUAGAAUAGUUUUUUCCAAAUCUGUGAAAAAUGACAUUGGUAGUUUGAUAGGAAUAGCAUUGAAUUCAUAGAUUGCUUUGGGCAGUAUGGCCAUUUUAAUGACAUAGAUUCUUCCAAUCCAUGAGCCUGGAAUAUUUCUCCAUUUCUUUGUGUCGUCUAUGUCUUUUAGCAGUGUUUUGUAGUUCUCCUUGUAGAGAUCUUUCUCCUCCUUGGUUAGAUGUAUUCGUAGGCAUUUUUUGUGUGUAUGGCUAUUACAAAUGGGAUUGCAUUCUUGAUUUGGCUCUCAGUUUGAAUGUUAUUGGUGUAUAGAAAUGCUACUGAUUUUUAUAUAUUGAUUUUGGUAUCCUGAAACUUUCCUGAAGUUAUUUAUUAGUUCCAGGAGACUUUUGAUGGAGUCUUUAGAGUUUUCAAGGUAUAGAAUCAUACUGUCUGUGAAGAAAAAUAGUUUGAUUUCUCCUUUUCCAAUUUGGAUUCCUUUUAUUUCUUCCUCUUGCCUGAUUGCUCUGGCUAGCACUUACAGUACAUGAAUAGGAGUGGUGAGAGUGGACAUCCUUUCUUAUUCCAGUUCUCAAAGGGAAUGCUUCCAGUUUUUGCCCAUUUAGUAUGAUGUUGGCUGUGUUUAUGUCAUAGAUGGCUCUUAUUAUUUUUUAGGUGUGUUCCUGCGGUGUCUAGUUUCUUGAGGGUUUUUAUCAUGAAAGGAUGUUGGAUUUUACUUAAAACUUUUUCUGCAUCUAUUGAGAUGAUUCUAUGGUUUUUGUUUUUAAUUCUGUCUAUGUGGUGAAUCACAUUUAUUGAUUUGUGUAUGUUGAACCAACCUUGCAUCCCAGGACUGAGGCCUACUUGAUUAUCAUGAAUUAACUUUUUUUGGUGUGUUGUUGAAUUCAGUUUUCUAGUAUUUUUUGAGGAUUUUGGUAUCUGUGCCCAUCAGGGAUAUCAGCCUUUUUAUUGUCUCUUUGCCAGGUUUUGGUACUAGGGUGAUACUGGCUUUGUAGAAUGAGUUAGGGAGGAGUCUCUCCUCAGUUUUUUGAAAUAGUUUCAGUAGAAUUGGUACCGGCUCUUCUUUGUAUGUCUGGUAGAAUUUGUGUGAAUCCAUUUCUGGUCUAGGGCUUUUUUGGAUUAGUAGGUUUUUAAUUAUUGAUUCAAUUUUGGAACUUGAUAUUGGUCUGUUUGGUGUUUCGAUUUCUUUCUGAUUCAAUCUUGGGAGAUUGUAUGUUUCCAGGAAUUAAUCCAUUUCCUCUAGAUUUUCUAGUUUGUGUGCAUAGAGGUGUUCAUAUUAGUCUCUGAGGAUCUUUUGUAUUUCUGUGGGAUUGGUUGGAAUGUCACCUUUGUCAUUUCUGAUUGUGCUUAUUUGGAUUUUCUCUCUCUUUUUCUUUUUUAAUCUAGCUAGCAGUCUAUAGAUCUUGUUUAUCCUUUCAAAGAACCAACUUUUGGUUUCGCUGAUUCUUUGUGUGGAUUUUUGAGUCUCAAUUUUGUUCAGUUGUGCUCUGAUUUUAGUUUUCUUCUGCUAGCUUUGGGGUUAGUUUGUUUUUGUUUUUUUCUAGUUCUUCUAGGUGUGAUGUUGGAUUGUUGAUUAGUAUCUCUGGGAUAUGGCUUUUGCUAUAUCGCAGAGAUUUUGGGAUAUUGUGUCUUUGUUUUUAUUUAUUUCAAAGAAUCUUUUGAUUUCAGCCUUGAUUUUAUUGUUUACCCCAAAGUCAUUCAGGAGCAAGUUGUUUAAUUUCCAUGUAAUUGUGUGGUUUUGAGAGAUCUUCUUGGUAUUGAUUUCUAUUUUUAUUCUACUGUGGUCCAAGAGUAUGGUUGAUAUGAUUUUGAUUUUUAAAAAAUUUAUCAAGACUUGCUUUAUGAUUGAGCAUGUGGUUAAUCUUGGGGUAUGUUCUGUGUGCAGAUGAGAAGAAUGUAUAUUUGUGGUCGAUAUAUAGAGUAUUCUGUACAUAUCUAUUAGUCCAAUUGGUCAACUGUUAAGUCCAGAAUGUCUUUGUUAAUUUCCUGUCAGUGGGGCGUUGAAGUCCCCUACUAUUAUUGUGUGGCUCUCUAAGUCUUUUUGUAAGUUUAUAGGUACUUGUUUUAUGAAUCUGGAUGCUCCGAUGUUGGAUACAUAUAUAUUUAGGAUAGUUAACUUUUAUUGAAUAUAACCCUUUAUCAUUAUGUAAUGCCCUUCUUUGUAUGUUUUUGCCGUUGUUGGUUUAAAGUCUAUUUAAUCUGAUAAUAAGAUUUUUUUGGUCUUUUUUUUCUGCCUUUUUUUUUGGUUUUCUUUUUGCAUGGUAGAUCUUUCUCCACCCCUUUACUUGGAGCGUAUGGGUGUCAUUACAUGUGAGAUGCGUCUCUUGAAGACAACAGAUGGAUGGGUCUUGUUUCUUUAUCCAACUUGCCACUCUUUGCCUUGUAAGUGGGGCAUUUAGACCAUUUACAUUCAAGGUUAAUAUUGAUAUGUGAAGUUUUGAUCCUAUUGUGAAGUUGUUAGCUGUUUGCUUUGUAGUUUCUAUUGUUUUUUUCUUUAUAGGGUCUGUGGGCUAUGUACUUAAGUGUGUUUUUGUGGUAGCAGGUAUCAUUCUUUUAUUUCCAUAUUUAGGACUCCCUUAGGGAUCUAUUGUAAGGCUGCUCUAGUGGUAACACAUUCCUUUGGCACUUGCUUGUCUGGAAAAGAUUUUAUUUCUUCUUUGCUAUGAAACUUAAUUUGGCAGAAUAUGAAAUUCUUGGUUGGAGUUUCUUUUCUUUAAGAAUGCUGAUAAUUGGCUCCCAAUCUCUCCUGGUUUGCAAGGUUUCUGCUGACAGGUCCACUGUUAGCCUGAUGGGGUUCCUUUUGUACAUAAUCUGCCCCUUUUCUCUAGCUGCCUUUAAGAUUUUUUCUUUAACACUGACCUUGGACAGUAUGGUGACUAUAUAUGUCUUGGUGAUGUUCAUUUUGUAUAUAGUAUCUUGCAGGUGUUCUCUGGAUUUCUUGUGUCUGGAUGUCUACCUCCCUGGCAAGAUAAGGAAAGUUUCCUUUUUUUUUUUUUUGACAUUUUUCACAAAUUUAUUUAUCCAUGUUCUAAGGACUAGGGAAGUUUUCUUGAAUUAUUGCCUCAAAUAUAUUUUCCAAGUUGUUUGCUUUUUCUCCUUCUCUCUCAGGAAUGCCAAUAAUUUGAAGGUUUGGUUGCAUUACAUAAUCCCACAUUUCUCAAAUAAUUUACUUAUUUUACUUAUUUUUAAAAAUUCUUCUUUUUUUUUUUUUUGGUCAGAUUGGGUUCGUUCAAAAGACCAGUCUUGAAGUCCUGAAAUUCUUUCUUCUGCUUGGUCCAGUCCAUUUAUAAAGCUUUCAAUUUUAUUUUGAAAUUCCUUAAGUGAGCUUUUUAAUUCUAGAGGCUCUGAUUGAUUUCUUUUUGAGAUGUUUAUCUCUUCAUUUCCUGGAUUGCUUUAGAAGUUUCUUUGUCUCAAUUUUUAACUUUGUCUUGGAUCUCCAUGAGCUUCCUUGCAAGCCAUGCUUUGAAGUUGUUUUUUUGUUUGUUUGUUUGUUUGUUUUUUUGAUACAGAGUCUCACUCUGCUGCCCAGGCUGGAGUGCAGUCAUGUAAUCUGAGCUUACUGCAACCUCCACCUCCCAGGUUCAAGUGAUUCUCUGCCUCAGCUUCCUGAGUAGCUGGGAUUACAGGCACAUGCCACCACGCCCAGCUAAUUUUUGUAUUUUUAGUAGAGAUGGGGUUUCACCAUAUUGGCCAGGCUGGUCUCGAACUCCCGACCUCAGGUGAUCUGGCCACCUUGGCCUCCCAAAGUGCUGGGAUUACAGGCAUAAGCCACCACACCCGGCCUAUGCUUUGAGUUCCUUAUCUGUUAUUUCUGAGUUUCUAUUUUGGUUAGGUACCAUUGCUGGAGAUCUAGUGAAAUUUUUUGGUGGUGUCACUACCUUCAGCUUUUUCAUGGUGCCAGAAUUCUUGUGCUGGUUCCUUCUCAUCUGGAGACCCUGGCACUUCUGAUUUUUGUAAUUAUUUUCAUGCACGUAGGAUUUUUUUCUUUUUCUUUUUUUUCCCUGUAAUGUUGUUGUUAUUAUUAUUAUUAUUAUUAAUUCUUCUUUCCUUUCCCUUUUCCCUGCUUGCCUAGGGGAUGUGACUGUAGAGAAUGCUUGGUAAGAUCUUUUGGCUUUGCUUGAACAGCCCUAUGCUGCUGCUGCUGCUCUUCUCCUUCUCCUUCUUCUUUUUUUUUUUUUUUUUUUUGGAGAUAGAGUCUCACUUAGUCACCCAGACUGGAGUGCAGAGUGCAGUGGCCUGAUCUUGGCUUACUACAACCUCCUCCUCCCAGGUCUGAGCAAUUCUCCUGCCUCAGCCUCCUGAGUAGCUGGGAUUGCAGGCACCCACUACCAUGCCUGGCUAAGUUUUGUAUUUUUAGUAGAGACAGGGUUUCACCUUGUUUGCCAUACUGGUCUUGAUCUCCUGACCCAAGUGAUCCGUCCACCUUAGCCUCCCAAGGUGCUGGGAUUACAGGCAUGAGCCACCGCGCCCGGCUGCCCUAUGUACUUCUUUCAGCAUGUUUUAUAUUGGGCUGUGGAGUUUGUCUUACAAGCCUGUAGAUGGCAUGCACAGGUGAGAGCCAGCUACAGCCAGUGUGUUUGGGUAUAUACUUGAUCCUUAUUUACUGGCAGAAGCUCUCUGUUGCUCCAGGCGAUUAGCUGAUUUGUAGAAUGCACAGUGGUCUGCACUCCUUGUUCAGCUCUGGUGGUGACAGGGGUUGGGAGGGUGGCAAUGGGAGCCGUGAAGGGCAGAGGCAGACCUGGCAAAUCUGCCUGCAGGUCCCCUGAUGGUAGGCACAAGCACUAGUGCCAAGAGAGAAUCCAGUGGGUGACCAUGAGGUACCCAAAGGUUUUCCUAGGUGUGGAGCUGGGAAACCUGCUCAGCUCCAAAUUCUCUGCAUGAGGAUGAGGAGAUGCCCUAAGCUCCUCAUCCAGGAGAGUGGGUGCUCCAGAUGCCUGGCGCACUGCCUGGACAUGGAGCAGAGAGGGUCUUGCUGCACUAUGAUCUAUACCCAGGAAGCGUGGGGCAGCUUAGGCUGCUGAACCAGAUGAGAGGGUGCUCUGAAUGCCUGGAGAUCUGCCUGGUUGUGAGGCAGAGAGGGCCUCUCCAUACCAGACUCUCUGCACAGGAAGAGUGGGGCAGGUCAAGCUGCCGAUCCAGGUGAGUGAUGCUCCAGAUGCCUGGAGAUUUGCCUGGGCAUGGAGCAGAGAGGGCCCCCGUGCACCAAGAUCUUUACACAGGAGGGGUGGGGCAACUUAGGCUGCUGGAACGUGCACGCAGGUGGUCUGAAUGCCUGGAGAUCUUCCUGGGCAUGUAACAGAGAGGGUCCCCCUGCACCAGGAUCUCUGUUCAGGAAGGGUGGGGCAGCUUAGGCUGCUGAACCCGGCAAACAGGUGUUCUAAGUGCCUGGAGAUCUGCCUAGGUGUGAAGCAGAGAGAGCCUCGCAGCACCGCAAUCUGUGUCCAGGAAGGGUGGGGUGGCUUGGGCUACUGGUUCAGGCAAGUACGUAUUCCAAAUGCCUGGAUUUCUGCCUGGGGUUGGAAGAGAGAGGGCCCUGCUGCACCAUGAUCUCAGGGAAGCAGAGUGGGGCACCCAAUAAUGGCACACACAGAUCAGUUGCAGGUUUCCAAGCUGGCCCUGGCUGCAAGUCUCGCCACCCAGGAGAAACUGCAGCUGUAGCAGCUCUCUUCCGUGCCAGGCUUGUGACAGGGGAGAGCACAAUUCCAGCACCUACUGCUGAAGCACUUUCCACAGUUCUGGAUGUGGAGGCCCCCUAUCCAACUCUGGAGCAGGUGUUCCAAUCUCUGGCCUGAGACUAAAAUGCCCAUACAGCCAUGCUGCAGGUCACCAAAGAAUGGCCGAGAUUAAAAAUGGUGUCCUGCUCUCAGUCUCAGAUCUGGGAAAAUGCCUGCAGCAUUUCCCAGUGUCUUUCCUUCACAGUGUCUCCAAUCCUCUCCUCAAGUUAACUCUCGGGCUUGGGAGAAGCAAAAUGCUUUCCCUUGGCCUGGGUUGCUUGGAUCCCCAGUGGAAAGGUGAGUCACAGAGGAGACUUCUUCCUUUCUCACAUACUGGGGCUUCACUCAUCUCUAUCAGCUGGAUGCUAUCAUGGGGGCUGUUUUCUGGCAUUCUCCUCCGUGGGUUCUGGGAUGUCCUUUAUGAUUCUGGUAGAUUUCCAUUUUCCUCCUUGAAUUAAAACUCACAGAGUUUAUCUUUAUAUACUAUCUUGCUAUUUCCAAGUGUCUGAGGCAGGCUGAAAGCCGCUAAUCCACCAUCUUGGAAAAAAGCCAACCAAAAACACUCAUUUUAUAUUUCAUGGGACAAUCUGGUUAAGGCUCUUGAACCUGAAAUAAAGAGGAUCUUGGAUCAGAUCCAUAGGAAUAGGAAAUUAUUUGAAAAGUUUCAGAUAAAAUAUACACAGAGAGAGUUCGUAUUUAAUUUCUUAUUUUUAUAAAGCUUCAAGUAAAUUAUUCAUUCAGCAAUUUUGUCAUUUAGGUAAAUAUCUUAAUGUCUACAUACAAGUAGAUACAUUUUUACUUUUCUUUUUUUUUUUUAAUCAGAAGAGACCUGGAUUAUGGUUUUUACUUUUCAAAGAUUCUAGUGUCAGGACCUGGGUGCAUUUGCACAUGUCUGUCAUCCUAGCUACUUGGGAGGCUGAGGCAGGAGAAUCGCUUGAGUCCAGGAGUUCAAGGCUACAGUGAGCUACAGUCAUGCCUAUGAAUAGCCACUGACUCUAGCCUGGACAACAUAGGAAGACCUUGUCUCUGGAAAAAAAAAAAUUAUAGUGUCAAGUCAUCAGAAUAGCUAGAAACAAAAAUCCAUGAUUUGAAAUUUCACAUACGUGAUUCUCACGUUUUAGGUACUGCAAUAAAAUUUUGUUAAUUUCAUGACAUUCCAAUAGGGAAAUAUAAUACGACUGAUUUAAGUGGAUGAAGACUCUGACAACAAAUUAAUAAUAGACUAGUAGGUUAAAUUAGUUAAACAUUUGAAAUUAAAUUAAUAGUUCAACUUGAGAAAUUUAUUCAAUCAAAAAUAGAAAUACAUUUUUAUGGGGAAAUAGACUACAUGAAUUGAAAUGACUAUGCUUCUUUGGCAGAUUAACAGAAGGUGCUAAAAAUGUCCCAUGCUGACUGACCCUAGAACUGUAAGAGCAGUGAACUUUGGAGUUUCUGGUUUUUAUUCACUGUUUUUUUUUUUUUUUUUUUUGAGAUGGAGCUUUGCUCUUGUUGUCCAGGCUGGAGUGCAAUGGCACAGUCUCGGCUCACUGCAACCUCUGCCUGCCAGGUUUAAGCGAUUUUCCUGCCUCAGCCUCCCGAGUAGCUGGGAUUACAGGCACGCGCCACCACACCUGGCUAAUUUUGUAUUUUUAGUAGAGACGGGGUUUCUCCAUGUUGGUCAAGCUGGUCUCGAACUCCCGACCUCAGGUGAUCCACCCGCCUUGGCUUCCCAAAGUGCUGGGAUUACAGGUGUGAGCCACCGCGCCUGGCUAUUCACUGUUUAUUAUAAUGAAAAUGCAUUAGAUAGCAUUAGAAUGUCAAAAUAAUACUAUUUUUCUUAGAUUAUCAGGCAAUGGCAUUAUGUGAUUCCUACUCAGACCAGCAUAUUCAUACUAAAUAAAAGACUGAAUAUCACUAGAAAGUUGGCUAACAGUUAUGGGUAUGCACGUACACACACAUACUAAUUUUAAUUUAUUAUUUUAAUGCUUCUAGGGGGAAAAAAUACAAUGUUCAUCACCUUAAAGGCCGACAAAGCAUUUGGCAAAAUUCAACAUUUCUUCAUAGAAUCACUUCAUAAAAUAUAAGUAAAUGAAUAGUUCCUUAAUAUGAAUACCAAAUGUAUGUAUCUUAGUUAAAAAGUCUGAAUUAUGCUUAGCAGGGAAACUAUGGAGGCAUUUCUGUCACAGUUAUGAACACAUCCAGGAUGACAAUGAUUACUUUUUAAUAUUGAACUAAAGUACAGACAGAUUAUGACAACAACUAGGUGGGAAGUGAGGGAAACUAGGAAAAAGCCACAUAUCUUGAUUGUAGAGUUGCAUCAGAAUUAGACCUUGUUCAAGAUUAUAUACACGUGCUUAAGAAAAUACCCUAAUAUGAGAACAACAAAAGAUACUGCAGCAAUAAAUCUAAUUCUUAAAAGGUGAAAGAAGCUGAGUGCCGUGGCUUAUGCCUUAUAAUCCCAUCACUUUGGAAGGCCAGGUGGGUGGAUCACUUGAGGCCAGGAGUUGGAGACCAGCUUGGCCCACAUGGUAAAACUCUGUCUCCACUAAAAAUACAAAAAAAUUUGUGGUGGUGCGCACCUGUAAUUCUAGCUACUCAGGAAGCUGAAGCAUGAGAAUUGUUUGAACCCAGGAGGCGGAGGUUGCAGUGAACUGAGAUCAGGCCACUACACUCCAGCCUGGGCAACAGAGCGAGUCUGUCUGAGUACAUAAAUAAAUAAAUUAAAUUAAAUUAAAAAGGUGAAAGAAUAACAUCCUUUUACAGAUGAUCUACUAGAGCAAAGAGAAGUAUGUUUUAGGAAUUUUUUGUUUUAUAUUAUUCAAAAAUCAGGAAAACAUAGACUCUGCAAUACAGAUGAUCCAAGCUGAGAAAAGACAACAGAUUGAGCUGAAAACUGAUUUACUGAGAUCAGCUGUGAUAAAAGAAAGCAAAAUGAAAUAGAAAGAGAUUGAAUUAAUUAAAAUUAAAUAAAUUAAAAUUUUCAGUAGAAGCACUGAACUGUAGACUUAAAACUGAAGAAAGUGAAAUCGGUCAUGUAGGAAAACUAACAUAAGAAGCUCUGCCAGAAUACAGAAAUAGAAUAAUAGAAUGAUGAAGAAAGGAAAAAGUCCUUUGGUUAUAAAUGAUAAUUUUGUUCCCUUUGCAGGGAGAGUUUACAGAUCUUGAGGGGCAGUGUCAUCAGUUGUAACACUGGUAAUUGGAGACAGAUACAGUCGAGCAUUUUAGAAUUUGAAAUAUGCCUUCUGCUUUUCAAAUUACUUGAAAAUCUUUUCUACAAAAGUAGAAAAGAUGAAAGAUCAAAGAAAAAAUAUUUCUUAGAGCAAAAGCUAGAAAACAGCAAAAAAGUAUGAACAAAAAAUGUGAAACAAGAUCAGAUAUUUCACUGACAGGGAAUAUAAAUGGGUUGAGUUCCCUAUUAAAAACGAAAACCUCUUCAGUAUAUGUAAGGCCAUAGCCAAAUGAUCUUUCUGCAGGUAAUAAUGAUAAAUUCUGAGCAAAAUACUCUACACAACUAUGUGAAGGUCCUGGAGAGUAAAAAAAAAAAAAAAAAAAGGCUGGCAGAUUCUUGAGGAAAGACAACACUUGGAAGAAUGUCCAGCAUGGAGAGUUUCCUGUUUUUCAUGAUACCAGCCUCAGGGCAGGGUAAAGUCAGUGCUGCAUUGAUACCUGCUAUUCUCAUAGAAAAUCCAGUCUUUCUGGCCUGAAAAACCAGAUGACAGAGUUUGCGGUAAGAACUACUGCUGGAAAAUGAGAAAUGGAUCCCAGAGAGAACUAGAUUGGUAUAGCCUGAGGUUCUGUGUGUAACCCCUGCCCAAAUCUCAGACUGACUUCUGAACCAUGCAUAUGCAGGGCAGACUAACAGCUACCCAACUAGGGGUAGGUCCAGAACUGAGAUUUGAGUUGCUGCCCAAGAGAAGAGUUUGUAGUUUGAAUCCAAGCAAGAUAAUUGCCUACUAAAGCAAAAAUAUCAACAUUCUUCAGUGAAGAAAAUGAAAUUCACAGUAUAACAUUCACGAGGUCCAGGAUACAAUCCAAAAUUGAAAAUGAGGAAAAUGUGUCCCAUUCUGAAGACAAAAAGCAGUUAACAGAGACUAUCCCCCAAUAUGAACUGGAUUAGCAGACAACUAUUAUAAAGCAGCUGGGGAAGCAAUUGCUGGGAGAGGGUGAGGUAAAGAAAAUAUGUUCAGAAUGAGUGAAAAGACAAGAAAUCUCAGCAGAGAACUGAAAUCAUAAAAAAUUUAAAUUCUAGAACUAUAAAAUAUAAUAUCUUAUAUAAAAAUUCACUUGAUGGGCUUAAUAGCAGAAUGGAGAUAACAGAGGAAAGGUUCAAAUAACUUAAAAUUAUCCCAUGUAAAGAAUAGAAAGAGAAUAAUUAGAAGAAAAGAAACAGAGCAUUAGGAAUGUGAGGAACUGUGCAAGCUUCUAACAUAUUUCCAAUUAGAAUCCCAGAAGACAAAGAGGAGAGAAUGAGGCAGAAAAACUUUUGAAAAAACAGUGACUGAAAAAUUUCCAAAUCUGAAACACAUAAAUUUAUAGAUUCCAGAAACUUAGUGAACUUAAAGCAGAAUAAAUUAAGCACACUUUAGUAAAACUGCUAAAAACCUAAGGUAAAGAGCAAAUCUAGAAAGCAACCAGAGAAAACGUGACACAUUAAAUAUAGAGGUUUUGGGAACAGGCCCCCAAAAUCUGGCCAUAAACUGGCCCAAAACUGGCCAUAAACAAAAUCUCUGCAGCACUGUGACACAUUUGUGAUGGCCAUGAUGCCCACGCUGAAGGUUGUGGGUGUACUGGAAUGAGGGCAAGGAACACCUGGCCCACCCAGGGCGGAAAACCGCUUAAGGCGUUCUUAAACCACAAAUGAUAGCAUGAGUGAUCGAUGCCUUAAGGACAUGUUCUUGCUGCAGAUAACUAGCCAGAGCCCAUCCCUUUAUUUCAGCCCAUCCCUUUGUUUCCCAUAAGGAAUACUUGUAGUUAAUCUAUAAUCCAUAGAAAAAAUGCUUAUCACUGGCUUGCUGUCAAUAAAUAUGUGGGUAAAUCUCUGUUCGAGGCUCUCAGCUCUGAAGGCUGUGAGACCACUGAUUUCCCACUCCACACGCUAUAUUUCUGUACGUGUGUCUUUAAUUUCUCUAGCGCCGCUGGGUUAGGGUCUCCACAAGCGAGCUGGUCUCUGCAUGGAGGAGUGAUGAUUGGGAACUGAUGACUUCUGUUAGAAACUUUGGAGCUCAGAGACAGUGGAACAUCUUUAAAAUGUUGAGAGGAAGAACCAUCAACUUAGAAUCUUAUUCUAGAACUUCCUGCGAGAAUGAAGACAGUAGCUCACACCUGUAAUCCCAGUGCUUUGGGAGGCUGAGGCAGGAGGAUUGCUUGGGGCUAGGAGUUUAAGACCUACCUGAGCAACAUAGUGAGACCCCAUCUCUACAAGAAAUUUAGAAAAAAUUAGCUGGUGUGGUGGCACAUGCCUGCAGUGGGAGCUUCUCAGGAGGCUGAGGUUGGGGAAUCACUUGAGCCCACAAAUUUGAGGCUGCAGUGAGCUAUAAUUGUGCCACUGCACUCUAGCCUGGGCAACAGAAUGAGACUCUGUCUCUCAAAUAAAUAAAUAAAAGAAUGAAGGCAAAAUAAAGACAUUCUAAGAUUAAAAAGAAAAAUGCCUCUCCUGGGCAUGGUGGCUUAUGCCUGUAAUCUCAGCACUUUGGGAGGCCAAGGCGGGUGGAUCACCUGAGGUCAGAAGUUUGAGACCAGCCUGGCCAACAUGGUGAAACCCUGUCUCUACCAAAAAUACAAAAUUAGCUGGGCAUGGUGGCGCAUACCUGUAAUCCCAGCUAUUUGGGGGGCUGGGGCAGGAGAAUCGCUUGAACUUGAGAGGCAGAGGUUGCAGUGAGCCAAGAUAGUGCCAUUGCACUCCAGCUUAGACAACAAGAGCAAAACUCCAUCUCAAAAAAAAAAAGAAAAGAAAAGAAAAGAAAAAUACCUAAGAGAAUUUAUCACCAACAAACUUGUACUACAAGAGAUUCCAAAACAUGUUCUUCAGGUAGAAGGAAAAUAAUGGGUGGGUACUUCAGUGAUGAAGAAGUGAAAUGCAUCAGAAAUGAAAAUGGUGAAUAGUGGGGUAAAUAUAAGCACUAGUUUUUUCUCUUAGUUUCUUUAAAAUGUAAUUGAUUGUUUUACAUAAAACUAUAGUGUUGUCUUAUAGAGUUUAUAGUGUAUGUAGAUGUGAUACAUGUGACACCAGUAGCAGAAAGGGGGAUGUUUAGUUGGUUCUAUACGAAUGCAGUGUUUCUACAUUUUUUUGAAGUGAUAUGAUAUUCUAAGUAGAGCAUGAAAAGCUAAGGAUGUAUAUUGUAAUCAUAGAACAACAACUAAAAUAAAGGCUGAUAGAUUAAAUUAAAAAGGAAUUUUAAAAUGUAUUCAAAUAAUCCAAAAAAUGUAGGCAAAAAGUAAAAGAAGGGACAGAAGGAAAACAAAUAAUAAAAUCAUGGACCUAAAUAUUAAAUGUUAAUGAACAUUCCAAUUAAAAGGUAGAGAUUAUCAGAACAAAUUUAAAAAAUACCAAGAGAUAUACUUUAAAAAUAAAGACACAGAUAGAUCAAAAGCAAUUGUAUGCAAAAAGAUAUAGCAUCCAAACAGUAAUGAUACGAUGGCUAACAUGGAUGUAUUAGUGCCAGAUUAAAUAAACUUCAGGAAAAGCUGGGCUUCUCUUUCACAGCAAAGAUGGAUUCUGAGGUGGAUGGGGAGUUCAGCUUCCCAGGGUGGCUUCCCAAGGUGGCGAAGGCUGUGGCCACACCAUGGUCUCAGAUGCUGAGGCAGGCCUAUGUGACUGCCAGUGGGUAGGCCAUGGUGAGUGGAGAAAACAGGCAGUUGUCCCCUCUGCAUGCCCUGCACAUACACCUGGGCUAUGGGCCCCACCAGCGGAUGUUUGUGCAGGGCUCAGCCUUUCCCUCGUUGGUUUCUGGCAGAACUAGGCCUGUGUCCCUUGUUCCUGGGCCAUAGUGCUGAAGUUUGUCUUCUAGGGAUUAGGUUGUAGAUAAAUCAAGUAUUGUAUGGUGGCUUGUGGAAGACAGUUUUGACUCUAAGAUCAGUUCAACAACCGUUAGCUUCAGCUAUAAUCAUUUAUGAUAUCAAAAAGAAGAAAUAUUUUCAACAUUAAGGAAUUGAUUACAUGAUUUUUAAGUUUUUUUUCUUUCUUGUAUCAAGGGACAAGUCAUAGAUUAAAAAAUUUUUGACAGCAAGCCCUAUCUAAUUUUAUAGUUGACAAAUGUGUGCUAUUAUCACAAAGGAGAAGUCAGAGAAAGAUGCUACAGACUGCGCCAAUUCAUUCAUACAAUUUUUCUGUAGUUCAAAAACCACAAUGUCUCACAUUGUCUAGCAGCUAGAAUUUUUUUAUUUAUUUAUUUUUUUUUUUAGUUUAAGAAAAGCAAAAGACCACAGUGAACUUAAAUGAACUCUUUAAACAAAUGAGUUGAAUAAUUCCAUCCACUUACACUAACACCCCAUCUGGUAGUAAGGCCUUUAGACUCCAAAGACAAUCUAGAGGCAAAGUGGAAGCUAUUGUUGGCUGAGCCUCAGUCACUCAUACUUCAUAAUGAAAUAGAUAGUUUUAAAAGUUAACAGGAUGAUUCUGGUCACUGCCAUUAGUUUGUACAUGGGUUUUGGGUCUUUUUCACACACAAAGGAUUCCCAGAAAUGUCUAAGUUUUGUUCUCUUUAUCAUUUUUUAUUGCGUCUAUUUGAUUCUUCUCUCUUUUCUUCUUUAUUAGUCUUGCUAGCGCUCUAUCAAUUUUGUUGAUCCUUUCAAAAAACCAGCUCCUGGAUUCAUUAAUUUUUUGAAGGGUUUUUUGUGUCUCUAUUUCCUUCAGUUCUGCUCUGAUUUUAGUUAUUUCUUGCCUUCUGCUAGCUUUUGAAUGUGUUUGCUCUUGCUUUUCUAGUUCUUUUAAUUGUGAUGUUAGGGUGUCAAUUUUAGAUCUUUCCUGCUUUCUCCUGUGGGCAUUUAGUGCUAUAAAUUUCCCUCUGCACACUGCUUUGAAUGUGUCCCAGAGAUUCUGGUAUGCUGUGUCUUUGUUCUUGUUGGUUUCAAAGAACAUCUUUAUUUCUGCCUUCAUUUCGUUAUGUACCCAGUAGUCAUUCAGGAGCAGGUUGUUCAGUUUCCAUGUAGUUGAGCGGUUUUGAGUGAGUUUCUUAAUCCUGAGUUCUAGUUUGAUUGCACUGUGGUCUGAGAGACAGUUUGUUAUAAUUUCUGUUCUUUUACAUUUGCUGAGGAGAGCUUUACUUCCAACUAUGUGGUCAAUUUUGGAAUAGGUGUGGUGUGGUGCUGAAAAAAAUGUAUAUUCUGUUGAUUUGGGGUGGAAAGUUCUGUAGAUGUCUAUUAGGUCUGCUUGGUGCAGAGCUGAGUUCAAUUCCUGGGUAUCCUUGUUAACUUUCUGUCUUGUUGAUCUGUCUAAUGUUGACAGUGGGGUGUUAAAGUCUCCCAUUAUUAUUGUGUGGGAGUCUAAGUCUCUUUGUAGGUCACUCAGGACUUGCUUUAUGAAUCUGGGUGCUCCUGUAUUGGGUGCAUAUAUAUUUAGGAGAGUUAGCUCUUCCUGUUGAAUUGAUCCCUUUACCAUUAUGUAAUGGCCUUCUUUGUCUCUUUUGAUCUUUGUUGGUUUAAAGUCUGUUUUUUGAGAGACUAGGAUUGCAACCCCUGCCUUUUUUUGUUUUCCAUUUGCUUGGUAGAUCUUCCUCCAUCCUUUUAUUUUGAGCCUGUGUGUGUCUCUGCACGUGGGAUGGGUUUCCUGAAUACAGCACACUGAUGGGUCUUGACUCUUUAUCCAAUUUGCCAGUCUGUGUCUUUUAAUUGGAGCAUUUAGUCCAUUUACAUUUAAAGUUAAUAUUGUUAUGUGUGAAUUUGAUCCCGUCAUUAUGAUGUUAACUGGUUAUUUUGCUCGUUAGUGGAUGCAGUUUCUUCCUAGCCUCGAUGGUCUUUACAAUUUGGCAUGAUUUUGCAGUGGCUAGUACCAGUUGUUCCUUUCCAUGUUUAGUGCUUCCUUCAGGAGCUCUUUUAGGGCAGGCCUGGUGGUGACAAAAUCUCUCAGCAUUUGCUUGUCUGUAAAGUAUUUUAUUUCUCCUUCACUUAUGAAGCUUAGUUUGGCUGGAUAUGAAAUUCUGGGUUGAAAAUUCUUUCCUUUAAGAAUGUUGAAUAUUGGCCCCCACUCUCCUCUGGCUUGUAGAAUUUCUGCCGAGAGAUCCGCUGUUAGUGUGAUGGGCUUCCCUUUGUGGGUAACCCGACCUUUCUCUCUGGGUGCCUUUAACAUUUUUUCCUUCAUUUCAACUUUGAUGAAUCUGACAAUUACGUGUCUUGGAGUUGUUUUUCUCGAGGAGUAUCUUUGUGGCGUUCUCUGUUUUUCCUGAAUUUGAAUGUUGACCUGCCUCGCUAGGUUGGGGAAGUUCUCCUGGAUAAUAUCCUGAAGAGUGUUUUCCAACUUGGUUCCAUUCUCCCUUUCACUUUCAGGUACACCAAUCAGACGUAGAUUUGGUCUUUUCACAUAGUCCCAUAUUUCUUGGAGGCUUUGUUCAUUUCUUUUUACUCUUUUUUCUCUAAACUUCUCUUCUCGCUUCAUUUCAGCUUCAUCACUGAUAUCCUUUCUUCCAGUUGAUUGAAUCGGCUACUGAAGCUUGUGCAUUCAUCAUGUAGUUCUCAUGCCAUGAUUUUCGGCUCCAUCAGGCCAUUUUAGGACUUCUCUACACUGGUUAUUCUAGUUAGCCAUUCGUCUAAUCUUUUUUCAAGGUUUUUAGCUUCUUUGAGUUGGGUUCGAACUUCCUCCUUUAGCUUGGAGAAGUUUGAUCGUCUGAAUCCUUCUUCUCUCAACUUGUCAAAGUCAUUCUCUGUCCAGCUUUGUACCGUUGCUAGCGAGGAGCUGCGUUCCUUUGGAGGGGGAGAGGUGCUCUGAUUUUUAGAAUUUUCAGCUUUUCUGCUUGUUAUUUCCCCAUCUUUGUGGUUUUAUCUACCUUUGGUCUUUGAUGAUGGUGACUUACAGAUGGCGUUUUGGUGUGGAUGUCCUUUCUGUUUGUUAGUUUUCCUUCUAACUGUCAGGACCCUCAGCUGCAGGUCUGUUGGAGUUUGCUGGAGGUCCACUCCAGACGCUGUUUGCCUGGGCAUCAGCAUUGGAGGCUGCAAACAGCGAAUAUUGCUGAACAGCAAAUGUUGCUGCAUGAUCAUUCCUCUGGAAGCUUCGUCUCAGAGGGGUACCCACUGUGUGAGGUGUCAGUCUGACCCUGCUGGGGGGUGCCUCCCAGUUAGGCUGCUCCUGGGUCAGGGACCUACUUGAGGAGGCAGUCUGUCCUUUCUCAAAUCUCAAACUCCAUACUGGGAGAACCACUACUCUCUUCAAAGCUCAGUUGGAAAUGCAGAAAUCACCCGUCUUCUGCGUCGCUCACGCUGGGAGCUGUAGACUGGAGGUGUUCCUAUUCGGCCAUCUUGGAACCCCCAUCACCCCACAAUUUCUUUAUGUAUUUGUUGAUUGAUGGGCAUUUGGGCUGGUUCCGUAUUUUUGCAAUUGCGAAUUGUGCUGCUAUAAACAUGCAUGUGCAGGUAUCUUUUUUGUAUAAUGACCUCUUUUCCUCUGGGUAGAUAUCCAAGAGUGGGAGGUAGAUACCCAAGAGUGGGAUUGCUGGAUCAAAUGGAAUUUCUACUGUUAAUUCUUUAAGGAAUCUUCACAUUAGUGGUUGUACUAGUUUACAUUCCCACCAGCAGUGUAGAAGUGUUCCUUUUUUACCGCAUCCACACCAACAUCUAUUAUUUUUUGAUUUUUUGAUUAUGGCCAUUCUUGCAGGAGUAAGGUGGUAUUGCAUUGUGGUUUUGAUUUGCAUUUCCCUGAUCAUUAGUGAUGUUGAGCAUUUUUUCAUGUUUGUUGGCCAUUUAUGUACCUUCUUUUGAGAAUUGUCUAUUCAUGUCCUUAGCCCACUUUUUGAUGGGAUUAUUUAUUUUUUUCUUGCCAACUUGUUUGAGUUCCUUGUAGAUUCUGGAUAUCAGUCCUUUGUCAGUUGUAUAAAUUGUGAAGAUUUUCUCCCACUCUGUGCGUUGUCUGUUUACUCUGCUGACUGUUCCUUUUGCUGGGCAGAAGCUCUUUAGUGUAGUUAAGUCCCACCUAUUUAUCUUUGGUUUUAUUGCAUAUGCUUUUGGUUUCUUGGUCAUGAAGUCUUUGUCUAAGCCAAUGUCUAGAAGGGUUUUUUUGAUGUUAUCUUCUGGAAUUUUUUGGAUGAAACAUUUUAAAAAGCCAUGCAACAGAAUGCGUUUCUAGAGGAUGCAUUUCUUGGUCCCUCAACUGCUUCAUGUCUUUUCUCACCUAAAAAGUAAUAAUAAUAAAAAUACAGCGUACAGUACAAGGCUCAACAUUGUAGGUAGAGACUGAAAGCCUGCCAUUGUUAAUGUUGUUUGCAACCAGCGUAGGUGUUCUGAUGAUGCUACCAUGCUGCUUACUUACCAUGAACACAUUAUUUUUUAUUGUAUUAAUGAUAUGUCAUAUUUUUUCCUGUUGAGUAUUUAUAUGUGAAUAAGUAUAAGAAAAUGAUUGCUGUGCUUGCUUUGGAAGCACAUAUAUUAAAAUUGGAAUGAUACAGAGAAGAUUAGCAUGGCUUCUGCACAAGGAUAAGUUUUAUUUAAAAGAUGUAAAAUUUUUUAAAAAAGAAAAUGUUUGCUUAUUGGUAGCAUAUAAAGACAGGAAUGAUGGUGAUGCUUAACAACCACAGAUUGUCCUCAUGGGUGGCAGAGAUAGUGAUACCUUCGCUUUCUGAUCAUUAAAUGUACACAGUCUUUGUUUCAUGCACAAAAUUAUUAAAAAUAUUGUAUAAAAUUACUUUUAGGUGAUGUAUAUAAGUUAUAUAUGGAACAUAAAUGAAUUUCUUGUUUAGACUUGGGUCUUACUUAUUAUGAUUUGUGUACAGUGCCUGGCAAAUUGUGUAGCUUCUAGUAGGUAUUCUGUAAAUCUUGGUUCCUCUUUUUAUUUAUCUGUUGUCUUCAGCACUCGUUUCAGUGAAGACAUAGUAGAAUUCAUCAAUGUGUGUUGAAUUGAAUAUCAAGCUAUAAUAUACUAUCAAAUGGGAACAUUUAAUGAGCUGUACUACCUACAGAUUUAGUAAAUUGUUGUUUGAACUUUAGUUCUUUUAAAAGAAGCUAUUUCAGCAACAGCUGCUUAAAUAGUCUAUAGGUAGUCUUUUCUUUUAGUCUGUAAUACAAUAAGAAUCUCCUAGAAGGAUAAAUCAAAUUGGUUCCAUGAAACCAUAAAAUUAUUGUGUGAUAAUUUAUAGGAAACCUCCUUUAACAACAUGUUUUAAAAGUUUUUGUUACUCUAAAUCGAUAUGUAUAUAUAUAAAUAAGCAUUAUUCAGCUUCUUGGUUUGACACUUGGAUUUUUAAGGAAAAGAUCUGCGUAUCCAUGUGCAUCUCCAAAAUAUUUAUUUAGGUACUUGUAAUUACUUUAAAAAUCCUCUUUGUUUGUGUUUCAUCUGUAGGUAUUAUAGCUAUUCACUGUUGAGAAUUUAGAGGUACUUAUACCAUUUUUUACAAAAUGAAUGUCCCAUAAUUCUAGCAUUCUGUUUUAUAUGACCAAGUGCUCAUUUCACUCUGUUUAGAGAUCAUGAAGGAAUCAUAGUCAAGAACUCCUGAAUUUUAAAAUAGUAUUUAGUAAUGACAAAUGUUGAUAUAAAUGUAUUAUGAAAUCUUUAUGUCUAAGAAAAAUAAUAUUAAACAGCUAAUAUUAAAAAUUUUGUUGGCUAAAUAACAUUUCAAGAGAUGGAUGUAUUGCAUUGAUAAUUAGCACGAUAUUUGAAUUACAAAAAACUCUUCAAUUUAAUGCGUAUGGUCCAUUUUCACUUGUGUUCUAUAAAAACCUAAAGGUUCUUAAGCCAAAUGAUUUCUGUUUAGAAUUCUGUUUAGAAUACAUUUCUCAGAGCAUAUAGUUUUGGAUGAUAUAUAUAUCCUUGUAAAGGCUGAUUUUUUAAAAAGUUCAUCCUUUAAAAAAUUAAGUCUGUAAGACUUAAAGGCAUUGGUAUUCUACUUUAACUUUGUUGAUGAGUGGAAAUCUUUUAAUCAAGAAUAUUACAAGUGGGUCUUUACAUCUCUCAUUGUCAUUAAUGAACUAAAAGGUGCAUACUUGUUAAACUACAUCUCAGAGCCUUAUACAUCCAUAAAAAAGAUGUUAUUCUACAAGUAGGACCAAAGUGUUACCUUAACAUAGAUGAACUUUCAUUAGUGUAGUAUCUUAGUUUUAAUUCUAUAACAUUGUGCUCUUUAAUAAUCACUAAUUAUAUGUAUGGCUUUUUUCCCAAUAAAAUUUUUAAAGG